AUUCUUAUGGACUACUUAGCAUUUGACUAGACGGUAUGAAUUUCUAAGUAAGGUAAGGAUUUCUUUCUAAGUUGUUUAUACCUAGAACUUAAAAGUGGGCAUGAAUAAAUCAAAUAUGGGUGGUUUUUAGUUGACACUUUAUUUUCCCGUUAGGAAAAAAUUAGUGACUGAUCUUUUAAAUUGAUUUAGUGCAUAUACUAUGUAUUGUGCAUAUGCACCAAACAAAUACUUAGUAAAAGGUUGUCUUGAAGGAACAUGCUGAUAUAUUUCAAAUAAAAGAACUUAGCAAAAAUGAGGAAAAUACCUAACAUUCUGGUAAGACAGUGAAAGAGGGAUGAGCAAUGUUUGUUUUGAAAAUUAUCUGCGAACUUUAAAAAAAUCUCUAAGAGUGUAUUCUUACUUGUAAUUGUUCAUCUAGUUACACUACAGAGUUUUAUUAGCUGCUCCAAGAUGCACUGCGUUCCAUUCUGUGGUGGAAACAAAAGGACCGUAGUAGUGGUUAUCUAGCAGAAGAAUCGUGAUCUUUGAAUUCUAAUACAAGAAACUUAGAAGUCUCCUAGAUAUUUCCACUGUCUCAGGGAAGAAUCAUUAAGUUUAUGUCAUUUUUUAAUAACUAAAACAAGAUUCAAAAAGUUAAGAUUCAAUUCUCAUUGGGUUUCUAUUGUUUGGGACUUUGGAUAAUAGAAAAAAAUAUGAACAGGUAAUUUAGGUUUUUUUGUGUUACUGGUACCUGACAAAACAAACUUGAGCUUCCCAUUUCCUAGAAACUUGGAGGAAAUAAUUUCUGUCCAGAAUGGCAAAUUGGUGUCAUAUCCCAUUAUAAGCAUAUUUUAAUCAAAAGAUGCAAUAAAGUGUAGUGGUCAAGAUCAUAGUCUCUAGAGUCAAGUAAUCCUUGGUGCAUUUACCUGCUUCAUCAUUAACCAGUUGUAUAUUUUUCUCAGAGCCAGUUUCCUAAUCUGUAAAAUGGGGGUAGACUAGUAUUGCUGUGAAGAUUAAAUGAAAUUUAUUAAAGUGCUUAGCAAAGUGCCUGGUAUGUAGAAAGUGUUUAAUAAAUAUUAUUAUUUCAGAAUAUAGAUGUAAAAGACAAAUGAUUUCCUAUAUAAUCAUAUUGAGUAGCCUGAAAGUUUGGUGGCUCUUAAAUAAAUCCAUGAAUGAAGGCUCUGCCUACUUUUGGCGUGUGGCCCACCAGCAUGUUCUAUCAGUUGGCCUGAGCUGGGAAAGAAACCAAUUCCUGUGUUGAGUUUUCCUCCAGGUGCUUAAAAUAGACCAUAGCUUAAUAUUUUGAUCAUUAACCAGUGAUUCUGGGUGGCUUCUCCUUGCUCUGGUCAGUGACCGGUGUAGGUCACGUAGUACAGCAUUAAACAAGGUGUUUUUCCUCCUGAGGUUGUCAUGUCAACUCUAAAUUCCCAGAGACUUGCCUAGGAGUGGAGAGUUUGUUCUGAGUUACAUAACCAGCAUUCUCUUUGAGGCUUUGAAUGUCUGUCUAACUGACUUCUGACUGCAGGCAUGCAAACUUUUCCCCUGCCUAGUAGGAAUGAAUACCCCUUUUCCAAGUAUCUGCAUAGCAGCGACCCAGGGGCUAUCCAAGAGCCAGUUGCUUCCUGACUUAAUUUCUGGGAAGACCAAUUGCCUAUUCAAGAGAAAUUCCUUCCUCCUUAUUCUUCUGUCAGAUGAGACUAGCUAUUAGGUAUUCCCUAUCUAGGACUCUGACCUGACUCUCCUAGAAAAGAAAAUGAGGAUCCAAGUCCAUUCCGUUUAACUGGGGCUAUAAACAUAUGCCACCAGAAAAAUCCUGCUAUUCUGGCUUAUUAUAACUUUAGGUUCUCCUUUCUAACACAAUACUAUCUUUAUAACAUGUACACACCUUUCCUUGGUAUUCAGUUGUAGUGUUUAUAUGUUCAAAAUCCUUCUAAUUUAGCCCCAACUAAAGUUUCCAGUAUAUAUUUGCAGGCCCCUUUUACUGCACCAUCUUCAGUAAAAUGCAUAUUUCUCUUUCUUCAGCAUAGGCUUCACCCUUAGAAGCUUGCUUUUCUCUGGAUAUUCAUUUCCAGCAGGUCUCAGAGAUAAUGUACUGUAUUGCAUCUUUUUCUGUUGGAGACUAGAAUGCAGUUAGCAGGUGCAGCUUGUUAUAAUAACUGCAGAUUCAGAUUUUUUCUCUCUGUAAAUACUGUUAAAUGUCCCCUCAGAGGCUCAUUUUAAAAUUGAGUAACGAAUGGGGGCUUGUUUUUCCUUAGUCCUCGAUCUUGGAAUCUUAGAGUCUGUCAUUGCACAUUGCUGCUUACCAUUUAGAGUUCAAACCACUAAUUCCCAAGUGAUAAGAGAUUAAGAUACAAACCUGAGAUAGGCAAAUGUACACUUGCAGCUUCCUUGCUUUAAUACUUCUGUUUCAGGUGGGAUGUCUUCUCCAUGGCUAUCCAGGUCUGUCCUAGACACCACCUUCGAGAAAUGAGAUCCUUUCUAUCUAAUUUAACCUAGAUUAGAGACAUCACCAAGAACACCUUCUGAAGCACAUAUAGAACUGGAUGCCCUUGUGGUACAUCUCAAGGCUGAUUUGAAAGCUUGAGAGACCAUCAAGAAUUGGAUUUGGGGAAGAGCAUGUAGGAGAAUACUAACCCUGCACAGAUUGUGAUGGUGAUGUGGAAUAUACUAAAGCCUAGAACGCACCUCCUCUGCAUGACUAAUAUGUUCUGCACAAGACAUGAAGGCACAGACAGCACUGUCUUUCUUCCUCAUUCUCAUAACAUCUCUGAGUGGAUCUCAAGGCAUAUUCCCUUUGGCUUUCUUCAUUUAUGUUCCUAUGAAUGAACAAAUCGUCAUUGGAAGACUUGAUGAAGAUAUAAUUCUCCCUUCUUCAUUUGAGAGGGGAUCCGAAGUCGUAAUACACUGGAAGUAUCAAGAUAGCUAUAAGGUUCACAGUUACUACAAAGGCAGUGACCAUUUGGAAAGCCAAGAUCCCAGAUAUGCAAACAGGACAUCCCUUUUCUAUAAUGAGAUUCAAAAUGGGAAUGCGUCGCUAUUUUUCAGAAGAGUAAGCCUUCUGGACGAAGGAAUUUACACCUGCUAUGUAGGAACAGCAAUUCAAGUGAUUACAAACAAAGUGGUGCUAAAGGUGGGAGUUUUUCUCACACCCGUGAUGAAGUAUGAAAAGAGGAACACAAACAGCUUCUUAAUAUGCAGCGUGUUAAGUGUUUAUCCUCGUCCAAUUAUCACGUGGAAAAUGGACAACACACCUAUCUCUGAAAACAACAUGGAAGAAACAGGGUCUUUGGAUUCUUUUUCUAUUAACAGCCCACUGAAUAUUACAGGAUCAAAUUCAUCUUAUGAAUGUACAAUUGAAAAUUCACUGCUGAAGCAAACAUGGACAGGGCGCUGGACGAUGAAAGAUGGCCUUCAUAAAAUGCAAAGUGAACACGUUUCACUCUCAUGUCAACCUGUAAAUGAUUAUUUUUCACCAAACCAAGACUUCAAAGUUACUUGGUCCAGAAUGAAAAGUGGGACUUUCUCUGUCCUGGCUUACUAUCUGAGCUCCUCACAAAAUACAAUUAUCAAUGAAUCCCGAUUCUCAUGGAACAAAGAGCUGAUAAACCAGAGUGACUUCUCUAUGAAUUUGAUGGAUCUUAAUCUUUCAGACAGUGGGGAAUAUUUAUGCAAUAUUUCUUCGGAUGAAUAUACUUUACUUACCAUCCACACAGUGCAUGUAGAACCGAGCCAAGAAACAGCUUCCCAUAACAAAGGCUUAUGGAUUUUGGUGCCCUCUGCGAUUUUGGCAGCUUUUCUGCUGAUUUGGAGCGUAAAAUGUUGCAGAGCCCAGCUAGAAGCCAGGAGGAGCAGACACCCUGCUGAUGGAGCCCAACAAGAAAGAUGUUGUGUCCCUCCUGGUGAGCGCUGUCCCAGUGCACCCGAUAAUGGCGAAGAAAAUGUGGUAAGGCAUUAUUUCCUUUAUCAAACCAUAUACAGUAUAAAAAUGCUUCUUUAAAAGGGUAAUUGAAGUUCUGACUGAUUCACAUAUCAUCAAGCAAGACUUUUAUACAGAAAAAAACAGCAGCAGGGGUUGCAGGAUAAUAUAGCACGAAAAAUAUAAUUAGGCUUUUCCCAAUGUCUAUAAUUAAACAGGCUCUACUUGCUUAAAUACAUGGUUGUUCUUCUUGUCUCCUAUUGUUAUUUGUAGAGAAGAUCUCCAAUGGCAUUGUGCAUAUGAGGGUGAGCCAAUGUACUUAUUCUUAUGAUAGAAGCAUGAAACAUGGGAUUGUAUACAAGUGGAAAGAAACACAACUAUAAUUCACUUGCAAAUUAUAGUUUGAUUGUAUACUUCCUUUUUACUGCAUUCCUUUUAGUAUUUAUGUGUUCCAUUAAUCAGAGUAUAAAUAAGGGCCAGGAGUGUGGUAAACUUGUUUUUUCCACUGUUAAAAACCAUGAAACAGCUAGUAGGGAGAUUAAAAUUAACUGAUAAGACUCAGACUUAUUUUAUAAUGGUCUCAUGGAUCUUUAAUUUCAGAUGCAAGCAAUAGACUAAAGCUUUUUGCCGCCCACCCCAAAACACUACUAUCAAUAAAUAUUUAAGAUAUAAAUGGUUAUUCUGACUUGAACAACAGACAUUUAGAGUCUAUUUUUCUUGCUUCUAGCCUCUUUCAGGAAAAGUAUAGGAAAUGAGAGAAGACUGUGACAACUCAUGACCUGCAUCCUUAAUAUCCAGUGACUUCAUCUCCCCUUUCUUCACCACAAUUCCAGGCAAUGGCCUGUCGGAGCAGACAAUUCUACCACUGCAAAGAGUUGUAACCAUUUUCUGGUAUCACAUUUAUUUUUCAAGACAUACUUUUCAAGACAUCAUUCACUGACCCACUACCUGCAUUGAGUAUAAAUGCCUGGAUGUUAAGGAUUCCAAUUUAACUUUGAAAAGAACUGUCUCAUUCAUUUACAUUUCUGUUACAGUCAGCCCAGGAGGUUACAGUGAGCUCUCCACUAAGAAUCUGGAAGAAAUGCAUCACUAGGGGUUGAUUCCCAAUCUGAUCAACUGAUAAUGGGUGAGAGAGCAGGUAAGAGCCAAAGUCACCUUAGUGGAAAGGUUAAAAACCAGAGCCUGGAAACCAAGAUGAUUGAUUUGACAAGGUAUUUUAGUCUAGUUUUAUAUGAACGGUUGUAUCAGGGUAACCAACUCGAUUUGGGAUGAAUCUUAGGGCACCAAAGACUAAGACAGUAUCUUUAAGAUUGCUAGGGAAAAGGGCCCUAUGUGUCAGGCCUCUGAGCCCAAGCCAAGCAUCGCAUCCCCUGUGAUUUGCACGUAUACAUCCAGAUGGCCUAAAGUAACUGAAGAUCCACAAAAGAAGUAAAAAUAGCCUUAACUGAUGACAUUCCACCAUUGUGAUUUGUUCCUGCCCCACCCUAACUGAUCAAUGUACUUUGUAAUCUCCCCCACCCUUAAGAAGGUACUUUGUAAUCUUCCCCACCCUUAAGAAGGUUCUUUGUAAUUCUCCCCACCCUUGAGAAUGUACUUUGUGAGAUCCACCCUGCCCACAAAACAUUGCUCUUAACUUCACCGCCUAACCCAAAACCUAUAAGAACUAAUGAUAAUCCAUCACCCUUCGCUGACUCUCUUUUCGGACUCAGCCCACCUGCACCCAGGUGAAAUAAACAGCUUUAUUGCUCACACAAA